AGUUUGUGUUUUGGAGCCUCUCACUUCUCCAGCGUCCCCGAUACGCCCGGGGAUUGCAGAGAACCCACACCUAUUCGUAGAUUAUGAGAGCACUCCCGGGGACCCAGCGCGGCGAAGCCCGCCAGGAUCGCGGGCGACCUGUGGCAGCUCUGGUUCCCCCGCCCGGGCCCGGCUCGGGUUACGCUCUGGGCGGGGACUCCGCAGCGGCUCCCUAGUUAGGGGGCGCCCCGGUGGGUUCCAGCUUUAGGGGUCGCAGGAGCGGCUCUGGCAUCACCUCGGAGCUGACGAAGCGGGAAGAGCCCCGCACCAGUGCUGCCCCUACAGAGCUCUCGGCGGGGGGUGGAGGUGAGGUUACACCUCGUCCCUACCCCCGCCUUCCCCUCCGCCGCAGGGAUCCGGGACCCGCCCCCGCGGAGAGGACGGGGGGCUGCGGGGAGGGGCUGUGCGGGGAGCGGGCGGGUUCCGCAGGCCCCUAGGUGGGGCGGGGCCCGAGCCAGAGUCGAGUCCCUGAGGCGGGUGGGGGAAGGAGAGACGGGUGGCGCGACCCUCUGUCCCCGCCUCGGGGCGGAGCCCAGGUCCCAGCCUGCGGAGCGCGAGACACGCCGAAAUCCGCCCGAGGCUACCUGUGCGACUCCAGCCGCCCUGCACCGGAAUCUGGGGAGACCCGCCCCCCGCCCCACCGGUCUGCGGCCCUCCGCCCCAGCGCAGGUGCAGGUGCGGCUUCUCUGCCCCUUUCACCCCAGGCGCAUCCGCCGCGGCGGCCAUGGCGCGAGGAGACGCCCCGCGGGACAGCUACCACCUGGUCGGGAUCAGCUUCUUCAUCCUGGGGCUGGGCACCCUCCUUCCCUGGAACUUCUUCAUCACCGCCAUCCCGUACUUCCAGGCGCGACUGGCCGGGGCCGGCAACAGCACAGCCAGGAUCCUGAGCACCAACCACACGGGUCCCGAGGAUGCCUUCAACUUCAACAAUUGGGUGACGCUGCUGUCCCAGCUGCCCCUGCUGCUCUUCACCCUCCUCAACUCCUUCCUGUACCAGUGCGUCCCGGAGACGGUGCGCAUUCUGGGCAGCCUGCUGGCCAUACUGCUGCUCUUUGCCCUGACAGCAGCGCUGGUCAAGGUGGACAUGAGCCCCGGACCCUUCUUCUCCAUCACCAUGGCCUCCGUCUGCUUCAUCAACUCCUUCAGUGCAGUCCUACAGGGCAGCCUCUUCGGGCAGCUGGGCACCAUGCCCUCCACCUACAGCACCCUCUUCCUCAGCGGCCAGGGCCUGGCUGGGAUCUUUGCUGCCCUUGCCAUGCUCCUGUCCAUGGCCAGUGGCGUGGACGCCGAGACCUCUGCCCUGGGGUACUUUAUCACGCCCUGUGUGGGCAUCCUCAUGUCCAUCGUGUGUUACCUGAGCCUGCCUCACCUGAAGUUUGCCCGCUACUACCUGGCCAAUAAAUCAUCCCAGGCCCAAGCUCAGGAGCUGGAGACCAAAGCUGAGCUCCUCCAGUCUGAUCUGGCUGACAGCGCUGUGCCUUGUGUUGGUCUUCACAGUCACCCUGUCCGUCUUCCCCGCCAUCACAGCCAUGGUGACCAGCUCCACCAGUCCUGGGAAGUGGAGUCAGUUCUUCAACCCCAUCUGCUGCUUCCUCCUCUUCAACAUCAUGGACUGGCUGGGACGGAGCCUGACCUCUUACUUCCUGUGGCCAGACGAGGACAGCCGGCUGCUGCCCCUGCUGGUCUGCCUGCGGUUCCUGUUCGUGCCCCUCUUCAUGCUGUGCCACGUGCCCCAGAGGUCCCGGCUGCCCAUCCUCUUCCCACAGGAUGCCUACUUCAUCACCUUCAUGCUGCUCUUUGCCGUUUCUAAUGGCUACCUGGUGUCCCUCACCAUGUGCCUGGCGCCCAGGUCCGGGGCAAUGGGGUGGGGUGGGGGGCUGGGAGUAGGGAGGUGGGUUCAGUCUUUGGGAAGGGACCGCCUGCAAUGGAGGGACGGCCCAUCCUGCUUCUGGCCAGCCCAACCCUAGCUGUCUGCAGGCCUUGCUGGCGCCCCCUACUGGGCCAAGCCUUAACUGCAGGGGAGAGAACUGGGCUAGGGAGGUACCCGCCCAACCAAGUAGCCCAGGCACUGGUUCUGGGGCCGCCUCAAUGUGCCUCAGUUUCCCCAUCUGUAAAAAAAAAUGGGUUGAACUGUCAUCCCUCAGGGCCCAUCUAACUGUAAAAUUCUCAGUUGAAGGAGAGCUAAGGUUUUGACCAAAAACAAGGUCAUGGGCUAUUUCCUCAAGGGGCAAUGGAGUGGAGAAUCCAGAGAGAAUGAAGCUGGCAGGGCAGACAGGCUGAGAGCACUGUGGAAAGGGCAGGCUGUGGAAUCUGGAAUCCCAUCAUGUUAGACUCAGAGGCCCUGAGAGACAUCCUUAUCCAGCAGCCUCAUUUACAGACCAGGAAACUGAGGCCCGGAAAGAAGGGGCCAGUUAUGGUGACAGAGGGGUUGGGUCAGAGCCCAGACUGGAUGGGCAGAGGGCAGUGGAGCUGGGUCCAGAUUUAGACCCAGCAUUUUCUAAGAGCUCCUGUUCCCGGGUGUUCUAGGCAGGUGCUGCCACACGAGAGGGAGGUGGCCGGCGCCCUCAUGACCUUCUUCCUGGCCCUGGGACUUUCCUGUGGAGCCUCCCUCUCCUUCCUCUUCAAGGCGCUGCUCUGAAGUGGCCCCUCCAGGCUCUUUGGCAGCCUCUUCUCGACGUCUCCUUCCGGAGCUGAGAUCCAGCCCAGGGCGAAUGGCGAGCUUGGCUCAGGCCUCUGCGGGGUGGAGGCCCCUGGGCCUGAGGCUGCCAGCAGCGGGCAGGAGCUGCUCUUCAUCCACUUGGAGUGCUGUGGGGAAGAAAUCACCACCGGUCAUUCUAACCCUCACCCAGGAAUGGGGGUGACUCGCACAAGACCUCAUGGAAAGGGUGAUGACUAGGGAAAAGAGGGUGCAGGGCACGGCUGCUCCCCACCACCAGGUCUGCAUUUGUUCAUCAUCAUCAGGAGCAGAGGUGACCAGAGGGUUCAGAGUGGGAGGCGGGGCCAGCCCAGGCCAGGAGCGCCUCAUCUUCCCAGGCCUCAGCCACCCAGGGUAAAAGGUGCCAGGGAAGUUGUGGGCACCUGAGAGGAGGAACAGAUGUGGAGGACCUGAGGGUGCUCAAAGGGCCAGGCUCAGCCUCAAGCAGUGUUUUCAUUGCCAACACUUACUGUACCCACUCCGCAGAGCCCAGCUGGGCCUGGGCCCCAGGGCCACAGCUAGCCUGCAUGUGUGUACUGCACUUUACAGUUUGCAAAGCUCUUCCAUACCCACUCUCUCACCGAAGCCUAAUUGAGGCUCUUGGAAGGAGUCAGGCAAGGAUUGUGCUUCCCCCAUUAUACAGGUGACAAAACUGAGUCCUGGGGAAAGUGACUGGUCCGUGGUAGAGCCGGGACCCAAUCCCCUCUCUCUCCUCCCUGUUGGUGCUGUUCUUCCUGCCCAACACCUGUUUCUCUUUUCCUCAAGGGGUUUGGGGCAGGAGCCUGGGCACUUACUCCCCGUUUUUGCUGUUUCUCCUUCUGACCCUGCUCUUGGGUCUAAUAACCCCAUUUAUUUGUA